GUGGCUCCUCAGAGCAAGGGAGGUAGUCGGGUCGAGGGAACCUGGCUCUGCCCAGGUGCCACUGCCCAAACCCCUGGGCCCCAUCCAUGGCAAGAGAGACCUUCCCCUUCACCUCCUCCAUGCUGCGCUCUCUCCGCCUGCAGCAGGAGUGGCUGGAAUGGGAGGACCGGCGGCGGGCGGCUGCCCAGCAGUGCCGGAGCCGCAGGUGCCCGUCAAGUCCCCGGGCCCGACUCACUAGGCCUCACCGUUCCUGCCGAGACCCAGCUGUCCACCAAGCCCUCUUCUCCGGCAACCUGCAGCAGGUCCAAGCCCUGUUCCAAGAUGAAGAGGCCGCCAACAUGAUUGUGGAGACUGUGAGCAACCAGCUGGCCUGGUCGGCUGAACAGGGGUUCUGGGUGCUGACCCCCAAGACCAAGCAGACGGCACCCCUCGCCAUCGCUACAGCCCGAGGCUACACAGACUGUGCUCGACACCUGAUCCGGCAGGGAGCUGAGCUGGAUGCCCGUGUCGGGGGUCGCGCUGCCUUGCAUGAGGCCUGUGCCCGAGCCCAGUUUGACUGUGUGCGGCUGCUGCUGACCUUCGGAGCCAAGGCUAAUGUGCUGACUGAGGAGGGCACGACUCCUUUGCACCUCUGCACGAUCCCCGAGUCCUUGCAGUGCGCCAAGUUGCUGCUGGAAGCAGGAGCGACGGUGAACCUGGCAGCAGGCGAGAGCCAGGAGACGCCCCUGCACGUGGCGGCGGCGCGCGGCCUGGAGCAACAUGUGGCUCUGUACCUGGAGCAUGGCGCCGACGUGGGCCUGCGCACCAGCCAGGGCGAGACUGCGCUGAACACGGCGUGCGCUGGGGCCGAGGGCCCAGGUAGCUGCAGGCGACACCAGGCUGCGGCGCGCCGGCUCCUGGAGGCUGGAGCUGAUGCCCGGGCGGCCGGGCGCAAGCGCCACACGCCGCUGCACAACGCUUGUGCCAACGGCUGCGGGGGCCUGGCCGAGCUGCUGCUGCGUUACGGGGCCCGCGCUGAGGUCCCCAAUGGGGCGGGCCACACGCCCAUGGACUGUGCGCUGCAGGCCGUCCAGGACUCCCCCAACUGGGAGCCUGAAGUCCUUUUCGCCGCACUGCUGGACUACGGGGCGCAGCCAGUGCGCCCUGAGAUGCUGAAACACUGCGCCAACUUCCCUCGGGCCCUGGAAGUCCUGCUUAAUGCCUAUCCUUGUGUCCCAUCCUGUGAGACCUGGGUGGAGGCGGUGCUCCCAGAGCUGUGGAAGGAGCACGAAGCCUUCUACAGCUCGGCCCUGUGCAUGGUGAACCAGCCAAGGCAGCUGCAGCACCUGGCCCGACUAGCUGUGCGCGCUCGGUUGGGAAGCCGCUGCCGGCAGGGUGCCACCCGGCUGCCACUGCCCCCGCUCCUCAGGGACUACCUGCUGCUGCGUGUGGAGGGGUGCAUCCAGUGAACCCCAUGUCAGGCUGUCCCAUGGUGUGUUCUGCCCCUCCCACCUGUCCCCGCCUCCAACUGCGGAGGACCAGUUCCUGGCCCUCUUUUCUUUUCUUUUUGAGACCUAGUCUCACUCUGUUGCCCAGGCUGGAGUGCAGUGGCGCUAUCUCGGCUCACUGCAACUUCUACCACCUAGGUUCAAGCGAUUCUUGUGCCCCAAACUUCCGAGUAGCUGGGACUACAGGCAUGAGUCACCACACCUGGCUGAUUUUGUAUUUUUAGUAGAGACAGGGUCUCACCAUGUUGGCCAGGCUGGUCUCACACUGACCUCAGGUGAUCCACCCGCCUUGGCCUCCCAAAGUGUUGGGAUUACAGGCAUGAGCCACUGCGCCUGGUUGCCUGCCCCUCUUUUCUGUACUCCACGUGCUGUCCUGGUCCACCUCACUCCUCCAUGGGCUUCUUGAGACACCUGCUGACCUCUAGCCGGACCUGAGCUUCAGACCCUCUCUCCAGCAGGAAGGGCUGCAGACUCGGCCUGUUCCCAGACUCGGCCUUCACCUCCCUUCUCCUCCUGUGUUUAAGUGGAUGGCCCCUCUAUCCAUCCAGGUCCCAUGCCAAGAACCAGUGAUUCUAGUGGCCCACCACCUCCCUCUCCUGCCACCCUUAUACCUGUUCAGCCUCCUAAAGAGGGACAAACUCUGUCUCUGCGUGCA